AGUGCAGCGGCGGCGGCGGCGGGGCUCUGCCUCUCCAGGAGCCCAGCGCAGGCCGCAGAGCCGGGGCCGCUGUGAGCCGAGACCGCGGGCCGCGGAGCUCGGGCGGCCGGCGCGGAGAAUUUGUUCCUGUUGAAGAGUGGCUCCUCUUCUAAUUUCCAGACUCCUUGAGGUUUUAGGAGUCUGGUAGGUGAAAUUUUCUACCUCUAAGGAGAAACAGUACCUGCUCCUUCCUCAAGCGCAAGCCCUCCAUUGCUAUGGAUACCGAAUCCACUUAUUCUGGAUAUUCUUACUAUUCAAGUCAUUCGAAAAAAUCUCACAGACAAGGGGAAAGAACUAGAGAGAGACACAAGUCACCCCGGAAUAAAGACGGCAGAGGGUCAGAAAAGUCUGUCACCAUUCAACCUCCCACUGGAGAGCCCCUGUUGGGAAAUGAUUCUACUCGGACAGAGGAAGUUCAGGAUGACAACUGGGGAGAGACCACCACGGCCAUCACAGGCACCUCGGAGCACAGCAUAUCCCAAGAGGACAUUGCCAGGAUCAGCAAGGACAUGGAGGACAGCGUGGGGCUGGAUUGCAAACGCUACCUGGGCCUCACCGUCGCCUCUUUUCUUGGACUUCUAGUUUUCCUCACCCCUAUUGCCUUCAUCCUUUUACCUCCGAUCCUGUGGAGGGAUGAGCUGGAGCCUUGUGGCACAAUUUGUGAGGGGCUCUUUAUCUCCAUGGCAUUCAAACUCCUCAUUCUGCUCAUAGGGACCUGGGCACUUUUUUUCCGCAAGCGGAGAGCUGACAUGCCACGGGUGUUUGUGUUUCGUGCCCUUUUGUUGGUCCUCAUCUUUCUCUUUGUGGUUUCCUAUUGGCUUUUUUACGGGGUCCGCAUUUUGGACUCUCGGGACCGGAAUUACCAGGGCAUUGUGCAAUAUGCAGUCUCCCUUGUGGAUGCCCUCCUCUUCAUCCAUUACCUGGCCAUCGUCCUGCUGGAGCUCAGGCAGCUGCAGCCCAUGUUCACGCUGCAGGUGGUCCGCUCCACCGAUGGCGAGUCCCGCUUCUACAGCCUGGGACACCUGAGUAUCCAGCGAGCAGCAUUGGUGGUCCUAGAAAAUUACUACAAAGAUUUCACCAUCUAUAACCCAAACCUCCUAACAGCCUCCAAAUUCCGAGCAGCCAAGCAUAUGGCCGGGCUGAAAGUCUACAAUGUAGAUGGCCCCAGUAACAAUGCCACUGGCCAGUCCCGGGCCAUGAUUGCUGCAGCUGCUCGGCGCAGGGACUCAAGCCACAACGAGUUGUAUUAUGAAGAGGCCGAACAUGAACGGCGAGUAAAGAAGCGGAAAGCAAGGCUGGUGGUUGCAGUGGAAGAGGCCUUCAUCCACAUUCAGCGUCUCCAGGCUGAGGAGCAGCAGAAAGCCCCAGGGGAGGUGAUGGACCCUAGGGAGGCCGCCCAGGCCAUUUUCCCCUCCAUGGCCAGGGCUCUCCAGAAGUACCUGCGCAUCACCCGGCAGCAGAACUACCACAGCAUGGAGAGCAUCCUGCAGCACCUGGCCUUCUGCAUCACCAACGGCAUGACCCCCAAGGCCUUCCUAGAACGGUACCUCAGUGCGGGCCCCACCCUGCAAUAUGACAAGGACCGCUGGCUCUCUACACAGUGGAGGCUUGUCAGUGAUGAGGCUGUGACUAAUGGAUUACGGGAUGGAAUUGUGUUCGUCCUUAAGUGCUUGGACUUCAGCCUCGUAGUCAAUGUGAAGAAAAUUCCAUUCAUCAUACUCUCUGAAGAGUUCAUAGACCCCAAAUCUCACAAAUUUGUCCUUCGCUUACAGUCUGAGACAUCCGUUUAAAAGUUCUAUAUUUGUGGCUUUAUUAAAAAAAAAAGAAAAAUAUAUAGAGAGAUAUAUAUCUAUGCCAGAGGGGUGUCUUUUUUAAAAAUUCUUCUUCAUUGCUGACUGAAACUGGCAGAUGAUUGACCAGUAUCCUUUGACCAUCUGCACUUUAUUUGGAAGGAAGCAGGGGCUGUCCACCCUGAAAAAGAGUGACUGAUGACAUCUGACUUUUGUCGAUGGGACUUCUCAAGAAGCCAUUCCUUGGAGCUUCUGUUACAGCUGUAAACCAAAGUGGAGCUGGUGCUUCUUGGGAGCCUCGCCUUACAACUAAUUCCUGCCUUUCGUCCAGUACCAAGUCCCCCGUUGCUUCUGGUCAGCCCACUUGUAGACUUCCAGGGGACACAUCUUUAUUCUGUUUCAGGAAACCAGUCACGACACGUCCACAUAUGUAUUUGUGUAUGUUAAUGUCCAGUAUCACAUCACCCAUGAAAGUCGUGGGCAGUUCAGGAGAUACCUGCCUUCAUCUUUGUUCUUUGUUGCCUUAGGUUCUUCAGAGAAAGAUCACAACAAAAAAUGUACACUGUCGUUUACAGCUAUUAAGUGAUUUGAUUUUGUUUUUUUCCCAAAGAGAAAACCUACCUGCCCUGUUUCUGAUCCCACCCCUCUGCUGGCUUGAAGCAGGUAACCCUUUCCCAGCCCUGCAGCUGCCCACCUGGCCUCCAUGCCAUCCUGCCCCCACCUGGCUGGCAGCCCUGGCUCUCCAUGUGUGCCCUCCGGCUCUGUGUGAAGCCUCAAGUCAGUCCCAGCAUUGUUUCCAUAGGGAAGUGUGGGGUGCCCAGCAGGUAAAGCACAGGGAGAGAGGGCAGUGGGAAUGCCACCUUUAGGCUGCAGCAGGAGCCCCACACUGCCCAGUUUUCCUCCCCACUGUUCUACACCAACCAGGGGAGACUAACACUGUGACUCUGGGAUUGGCAGGUGCAACUUGGAGCCACUUAAUUUCCUGGGGACGUAAGUUCUUCCCAAGCUUAGAGCAAGCUGCCCUGCCAAAGGAGACCAAACCAUGCCAACCACGCUGGCAACUGCUGCUGUCCAGUCCCUGUGUUUUCUGACCACCGUCACUGUGCAACUCAUCGCCUCUGCCACUUAGGACCAGGAAAGAGGCUGGUUUUGCUCCCACUCUUAGUUGCUGAUAAAGUGGGGAGAAGGAAAAUGGACACUCUACAGAGUUUGGGGAAGGGAGAGUAGGGAGCCCAUCUUGUCCAGAAAGAUUCAUCUGUGGUCUGUCUGUUAAACACAGCUGAUUUCAGUGGGCUUUCCCCUGGCCCUGGGGGAGCAGACACUGACUGGGUUGUGGGCAGAGGAGCCAUCCUGGCGGAGCCCUGCUGCAGGGGAGCUCCUUCAGGAGCCCCAUCCGGACCUCUUGCACUGGGCUGCCUUUGCCUCCAUUUGCCUUCCUGUAUCUGCAACAAACCUUUUAAAAGUGUUCACUCUUGCUUUUUCCAGUAUUUCGGUAAUCAGCCAUCUUGCUGUAGUACAGGAUGACAUUGUCGAAUGCUCUUUGUAUGUGUGCACACCCCCUUACUCCCUUACUGCUUCAUACACUCCACAAGUGGUACAGUAUUUUGUGUCAUUGUAAAAAUCAAAAUUGGCUUUGGAUCUUUGUAAUACACCUGUACCUGAAAAAGUAAACAACAUUCUUCAAUUACUAGCCUUCAGCUUGAAAAGACAUGCUGGAGAAGAAGGAAGGGGGAACCCAUAGGUGUGGCGUGGAGCCAAGAUGUACUAUUCAACUAUGUGUUUCUGUUUAUAAAAAACACAUACCAUGGAACCAUGGUGCUUUUGUUCUUAGUUUUUGCCGUUAGAUCCCUUCAAACUGGAAGUUCCUUACAAUAUCUUUCUCAGGAAAUAUUUUGGGAAAUGGGGUAAGAGAUGGCAAGUGUGAGACGGGCUGUGUCAGAGGUUGCUACGUCAUGGAUACAGUGCAGUUCCAAGUGCCAUAAGUGUAUGUACAUAUAGUUAAUAAUGACACUGUUCAUCACCAUUCUAAAAUACUGUUCUUCCAACCCUAUCUUCAAUGACCAGUCCAGAAGGGGUUAAGCUGGAUUCAUUUGCUCUGGCAUGUGCAUUCCCAGCAGGGUGAAGAAAGGUUUAAAUUAAAGAAUUUAUUUUCUCUCUCCCCCUUCCUCUUUCUCCCAGUCUUUGCAUAGGAGAAUGUUAGACAUUCAGAAAUUACUGUUUCUGUUUUAAAUUGAGUAUUGAUUUUUUUAUAUUGACUUUGUAUUGAGUUCUUUUUGAAAGAAUAACAAAAUAAAAUGCAGGAUCUUUGUAAAGCCUUUGCACUUUCAACCUCUUUAUAGCUUGAGUUACUUUUGCAGUGGGAACAAUGUAAAUGACAUUUAAAAGAUUUAAGGUUUCAGAAAGCUGCAUCCCACAAUUGAACACAAUGCAUUUUUAUUUCAAUUCUUGGAACUGGUAGGCUAUUCUUUUUAAAAGGGGGUAAACUUCGCCCUAAGGCUGGUAGAAUGUAUGUUCACAUUAUAGUAGACAGGAUUUCAUUUGCCUUAUAUGUUUAUAGAUUUUUUAUAAUUUUCAUCCUACGUUAUUAAAAUUAGAGCAUUGAGUGUUAAAGAACUUAAUGAGGAGUCUAUAUCUGAGAUUGCUCUCUUCCCUGGUGAUGUUUUAACUGGUAGAUAAUUUGUUCUUAAAUAUGUACUUUUGAAGAUAGGACAGUUUUUAUAGUCCAUGAACUGAAUGUUAAAAAGUUCUGUAUGCAUUCUCAGAGAGGAUUUUAAAGCUAUAUAGUUCAUCCAUCCUUUGCAUUAUCAAAAUGUUAAGUCAAAUCUGUAAUACUUUGGCUAAAAUUCAUAAAGUAAGCCCUAGAGAAAAUACUUGACCACCAAAUUUUUGCCCAACUAUCAUCACCUCCCUUCCCCCGCCUCUGUUCUUGCCUUUUGACAUCUACAUGGAAGACAAGUUCUUUACAGCAAAUGGUAAGAGGCAGGUGACCUGGUGUGUUUGCUGUGUUGUAGUUCAUUGCCUGGGGCUUGGGACUCCUUUUUUAAUGGAGAGACUAGCUGUGCAGGUGUGUGUUGGAUAGGGAUAAAGUGCUCACCCCUGCCCUCUCUACAGUAGUUGGUGGUAGAUUUCUCUCUCAUUUUGCCUCAUAAUCACUUUCGAGUGCAUGUAUUUACCUAAGGGCUGUAGCUCUGUGGGAUGCUACCAGCAUAUUGGACUGACAGAAAUUGAUUACCUUGCCACUCCAACCUACGUACUGAGUGAGUGCUCCAGCCACUCAGUGAAACCAACAAAAGUGAGUCCUUGGUUUACCUUCCAAUCUGGGUCCUGCUGUGUAAGUAUCCCUAAGUGGGGAUGCAUAUUUGUUUGUGCGUUUUUAUUUCCAUAUAUGUGAGCAUUUCUCUGAGUGUAUUACCAGACGGAUAGCACAUUUAUAUGUCAGACAUCUUAACAUCUGUGUUAUCUGUAGCAGGUGUGUAGCUCAGCAGAUACGUGUCAUUGUGUAUAUAGCUGAGUGUGUGAGGGUGUCUGUGUUUCUGCAGUCCCCUGUGUUUGAGAGAUGACUUAAUAACCCUGUGUUUUGAGAGGUCGCUCUAAACCAGUGACUUUUCCCUCCCCUGCUUUAUUCCUUUCCCUCACUGACACUGGCUUCUCCCGCUAGAGUAAAUGGCUUUAGCACAGCACUGUCUUCUGGGGAGCCUGCUGUCCUGCAGGCAAGUCCAUUAAACUCUUUCUUGCUUUAGGACUCUGAAAACAGCAAGAAACAAACAAACAAAGGUCAAGCUCUAAGAAAAUUACUGCUCAAACUUCACUACCCUGGAAGCCUUACUAGAUAUUUCUUAAGGUAACUUAAAAAUUGGGCUUUAUUUUUAAAAAGUGAUAGGUUACUUACAGUAGCACAGAAAUGUUAGCAUAUUUAUUUAAAUAGUCCUGCAGCAGAGACCCUGCGAUUGUAAAGUGAUUUAAGUAUUUCUGGGUAGUGUUUGUGAUUUACGGAUUUGUUACUGAAAAACAAAAAAAUCACUACUGUGAAUUUACUACUAUGUAACCUUGUGGUCGUAUUUCAUUAUAAAUAAAAUAAGAAUUGCUCUUCUGCCCACCGUUCUUGAUUGGUAUUCAGUGCAGUAGCGAAAUGAGAUAGUUUAGACACUGUUGAAAUAACUGCAUUGAGCUUUAACCAAGUGUAUGCUCAGAAAAUUCAGUUUUGGAUCACAUUUUGACAAAACAUGUUUUGGUCAAAGAAAGGAAAGGCUACUAACACAUUUAUCAGGUAAUGUAUGUCACAGUCCGUGUUCCACCCAGCCUUGUUAUCCCCACAUUCUUUCAAGAUAGGAGUCAUCUUGGUUUUUCGGGUGAAAAACGGAAGGUCAGAGAGGAAGGGGCUUGUCCAAGGUCUCAUGUCUGGUUAACAGAAUUUCAAACUAGAUGUUUGAUUCUAACCCCUCAGUCCACUGUACCUUGAAGUAUGGUCUAAAUGAUUCGGCACUUCUGGAUGUUGAGGAAGGACCUAGAGACACAUCCUUGAACUAGAACCUGGGGUGAGAGUUCAUUGGGAGGCAGGAUCUCUUCUUUCACUUUGGAUUUACACCUUGUCCCUUGGAAAGCUUCUCCACUAUGCUAGCAAAUAUCUUAGGAUAUUUGAUGGAAAGAACUUGAGAAUCCCUUCUGGAAAACCCAGCCUUUCAGUGUUAACACCUGCUGCAAGACAGGGAUGCUGUUGUUCUGGCAGCCCCCCUUUGCUUUUGCCUGGCCCCACCUUCUGCUCCCACUCUGCUGGCUUGGGCAAGAUGCGUGCCUUGGGCCUUGGGUGCAGGGAGGCAGGCAGGGGCUUGACCUGGCCUCUCUCUGGUGCCAUGGCAACAUUAUGCCCCAAACUUCUUCCCUGGUUGGAGUGAGAGGGGCUGUCCACAGCCCCAUCCUGUGGGGAUCUCAAGCCGGAGUCCCUGGCCUGGCCUCCUUGACGUAGGUGUUCUCAGCAAGCAGUUUGCAUCCCACCGUCUUUCUCACACUUGCCCCCAAGACUUUUGACAGAGCAGACGUAAAACAGGACUCAGAAAACCAUUUUUCUCUGUUCCCAUAUGUAGUAAGUUUUGAUUCAGUUGUGCAUAAACCAUAGUUUUCUGCCCUGCUGUUUGCUUUCAAUGGAAGACAGUAAAGGGAAGAUGGUGCUCACAUCUCUCCAUGUGACAUCUCAUUAGGAAUUAAGAUGCGAUGGAUUAGAAAUGUAAAACUUCAGAAUAAAAUUAAAUUUCAGGGCUCUAUAAGUCCCGUUUUCCCAGGUCCUGUUCCGUUUCUACGUAGAUAACCCAAUUUGUUUUGUCUAUGAAAUAAGCCUCUUUAGUGGGUUGUUUUAGUCUCUCCAACAAAAGAGCAGAUUCCUAAAGCCAGGUGCAGCACUGUGAAAAGUUUCUUUCAAUAUGGCACCAAGACUCUACCAUUUAUGUCUCUCUCAGCUUACAAACAUCAGCGUUUUGUCCUUGUCAUAGUGGAAGAAAGACACUUACUUUAAGCUUUGGGGACAAAGGUGACAAACCCCAGGCUUUUAUCUUAAAAGUGUCUUUGGCACUUCUUUUGGCACUGAAAUGGUAUUUGGGAAGCAUUAUUUGAAUGUACAGUUGUUUGGUUUUGUAUGUGCUUAUCUUUAUCUGAGCUUUCACUUGUAGACAUGGCCUUUUGUUGUGAAGUUGCUCAUCAUUUAGGAGUGUUUAAUUCUAAAAAGCCUUCAGCCUAAGAAAGCUUCAUCUGUGGGGACCAGAGACUUGUUGCUCAGGGAGUUAGUGAUGGGACUUGGGCAUCUGAUCUGCAGGUGACAAGUUUAGUUCAACUGAAGUUGUAGGGAAUUUAGACAGUUGCACAUCAUUGCCGUUCUAGGGGCCUUGUAGAAAGAUGAAACAGUUGUUUUUCAUUUACCAGCACCUCUCAGUUAUAGAGGUAAUGGAACAUUCGCUUACUUUUCAUCAUCAUUCUUUAAAAAGGGAACAUACAAAAAUCUAAACUAUGGCAAUAAUUUAUUUUUAUAAUAGUUUACGGUAGGCUUUAAUUAAAUGGCAAACUCCUCUGGGACCCCUAAGUUAUGGCGUGAUUAGCCAAAUUUGAUUUCCAACAGUCAUUUAUGGCCAUAACUAUUGCAUAGAGUGCAGGAUGCCAGCAAAGAUGAGGGUGGGGGCAGAUACUGGCUCAGUGAUUUAACUCACAUUAUAGAUGACCCCUUCCUCAACAGAAAUGCUACUGAGAGAACCAGAGAGGCCUGGGCCAGGCAGGUCUUAUUUGAGAGGAGAUUAUUUGAUAAUUGCUUUGGUUAGAAGGACUUUACAUUUCCUGAUUUCAAGUCCAGCACCAAUUUAGAAAGUUCAGAGAUGAAACCACCUGUCUUUACCUGACAGAGUCAUAACGGUUUGUGUAAAAAUGUGGUCAGGGACCUUUUUUGUUCUUUCUGAUUAGUUAAUACUGUACAUUGUAACCAGGAGGGGCAGUUUUGCCAACCAGCCUCUGCUCAUGGUCACCAUAUGUGUAUGACAAGGCCUGAGUGAGUUCCUGCAUAAACUGGGUAGUGGGCUCUUUUGACACAUUUGCAAGCAUGUAAAUGAAUGAAUGACACUACCAGCAACCAUCUGUACAGGUCCAUUUACUUACAUUCAUAAGGUUUAUGCUAUGAAACUUCUUCUCAUUGUGAUGUCAGUAACAGAGUUAGUGUCUCUGAUGGAAUAGUGUACCUGUCACCCAAGUUAUUUUGUUCCUUUUUGGGUCCUCCAGUAUAAUCCCCCCCUCAUCCCAAUUAACUGUAAAAUGUUUUACACAUCACAUUUUUUAUACUGUAAACUUGGAAAAUAAACUGAAAUAUCAAA